GGUCACGUGUGUACACAGGGCCCGGGCGGCGUGCGCGCCGUGAGCCCCGCCGCCUCCGCCAGCCCGAGCUGCCCGCCCGGCGGCGACUGCGCCGGCCGCCGCCCAGCAAGCCGCCUUUGAUCUCUUCCCUGCCCAUGAAGAUGUACUUGAGUCCUCCAUUCCACUUUAAAUAGCCAGCUCCUGUCCACACGGAACAGCACGACAUCUUUUAUCUUUUGCUACCUGCAGCACCUAGCAGAGGCCAGCAUUCAAUAACAGAGGGCCAAGAGGCUUGCUUUAAAGGCCUCUGCAAACUUGUAUGAGUAAAAUGGUUCUGACCAUGUUCCCAGGCUCCUCACGCAUAGUGGUGAUGAGAUAGUCUACCGUCCUAACUGGGGCACCGUUGAGAGUGAACGGAGGCACUGUUAAUAAUUAGACGAAGUGCACACUCACAGUACCCAUGACCUGCUGUGCAGCUCCUUCAAGAACUACUGUAAGGCCUGGCUCCCCAACCAGAACCCCUGUUGUCUUCCUCAAUGAAGAAGGCCUCUGAAGACAAGUGACUUAAGAACAUAGUUUAUAUGUAUUGAAUACUGUUGUGCCUUUUCACAGAGAAGAGGUCGGGGCCAGAGCAGCUCACUGCCCGACGCCACACACAUCCGUGCUGGCGUCCACGUGUCAUCCUGCCUCUCUAGCCAGCAUGGACAUAUCCUGAGGAUGGAGGACAGAGGAACACAGAUUUAGGGCAGAAUGUAAAUGUGAAAGUUGACUUGGAGUCCCUGCAACUCAUAAGCCCCAGUAGGCUGAUGAAGAGAGAAGGGCAAAGGGCGCGCACCUCAUGUGGGUCUUAGGUUAGGAUGUAAAGGCUGAUUAUGUCUAUCAUACAAUGAAUCAAUGGCAUACUGCACAGAUCGCUGCAUGGGGAAAUAUGCUCGUGUAAUUUACAGUCGGAAGAGGGACAUGCUGCUCACUGGGGCAGGGAGAAGAAGGGGCUCCUCAGGGAGCUGCAGCUCUCACAGCCCCUAGGAUGUCACCUGGAAUCCUGAAAAAAUAACUGCCGCCUGGCCUUUAAUGACCCAACCACAGCGAGGUCUUGCCUUUGCAGAAGGAAAUUAUCACCCAGAGAACCCGGCCGACCGUGUCAUGCACACGACGAUCCCACGGUGCUGUUUUCUGUCAACAGUGUUUCCCAGCCAUUCCCUCCUGCCUGCCAGCUCCUCUGCUCUCCAGGGCUUUCACUAACCCACCUGCCCAACUGACCAGCAUUAGGCUGUCCAGUUAGCCCACAUCUGUCCAGGGGUCUCAAAGGCUCAGGACCCCAAGACACCAUCCAGGUAGCCAAGAGGACAGGGAACCCAGUCUGGAGAGUAGAAUAACGUUUCGCUCCAAUUUGAGAUCCCAAAAUGAGAUGCUGCCCGGGACCAGAAGUCAGUUUCUUAGGAGCGUGCUGUCUACCCAGGAGCCUCCGUGUGCAAACAAAAUACCCCCUUGAGCAGCAGAGGGACAAGGUGGAGGUGGGGCAGGUGUCUGUUCAUCCCCACAGAGCCACACCCAGGUCCCUUCCUGCAAAGGCCAAGGACUUUCCCCAUUUUAAUUGGAACCAAAGCAAGCCUUGCAGACCACUGUCGCUACCACAGCUAGUGUGAUGAGGAGAAAUAACCUGCUGGCUCCUCCCUGGGAAACAACCAAGGUGGUGAUAAGAUCUGCGGCUCAGAGCACUUCCCUGCAGGUUAAGGCCACGCCUAGUAAACCGGGGCUCGACUGAGGAGCCCCGGCAGGUGCCAAGCCUGCCCAGAGUCUGCAGUAGAGACUCUCUGUUCUUGGCCAUGUCUUUGAAUUUCUGAGGAAGUCUUUUUUGUUUGUUUUUGUUUUUCCCUGGUCUGAUGUACCUGGAGAGGGAAUUAGCCUCACACCCAGUUAGGGAACAAAAAGCCAAGUAAACAAAAGAAUGCUGUUCCACCUUCCUCCAGGGAACUGGCGCCCAUAGCUGCAGGCACAGGUGCCCAGCCCGCUCACUGGCCCAGCAAGGUGCUUGGUCUCAGGCCCCCAGAGCCCGUCCUGGAGCCGCAAACAUGCUCGCUAUUAUCCAUGGAAAAAGAGAGGCAUUCUCUUUGUUUAUAGUCUAAGCCAAGUCACCUGAUUCACUCUCACUACUCUGCAGUUUGGAAUUGUAAAAAGCAAAAGGCUACAAAAAUCAAAACCAUCCACCUAUGUAAUGAACCAUUUCUUAUCACAGCCCAGGAAGGCACAGAUAGGAAUCAGUGUGCGUAAGCUCUCCACGUGGAAACCCUGUGAAAACAGCAGCCUUUCCUAAGCAUCUGGCUCCUAGGAGCUGGAUGUUAAUUGUUGCUAAAGCCUGGGUUCAUUACUACAAAAGAAAAUAAACAUUCCAGAGUCAUUUUGAAAGCAUUUUGAUUGUUCUAGAAUAUUCACCCAAGGUUGAGCGUCUCAUGGUGCAUGGCAGGUUCGGCCAGGAGCUGGCCGUGGCCUUUCCACUCCUUUCCUGCCAUCCUGAGGAUGCAGUGCCUGGGGCCUCGCAGUUCUCUUUCCACUCAAAUCUAAGGCUCUAAAGCUUCAACAACUGUCCGGGGACAAUAAGAAGCGCUGAGUCCCCAUCCUGCCUGCUCUCCUUUCUACUCAGUGGGGAAAUUGGAUCACUCGCCUUGGUGGAUCACUCGCCUUGGGGAAAAGCCUUUUACGUCACUGAAUACAUCCCCUUCUACGGUUUUCAUCCAACAGUCAGCCAGGCUGCUGCAGCACACAUAAAAACUUCCCCUGCCUGCAAAGAGCUCCAAGUAGGUGGGAAAGAGAUGGAUGUGCGGACAGGCUUAACCCAGCAAAGACUGGCGGAGGGGUGUGGAGACAGUGGUCAGGGGUGGGUUCCCGGGGGUACUGAUGCCCAAAAUAAAAUGUCAAGGACGAGCCAGUGUUUGCUGAGAGAACGAGGGGAAGCGAGAAAGGGUGUUCUAGGCAAGGGAUCAACAUCCGCAAAAGACAGUGUGAAAGAGAGCACCCGGAAACUUCGUGGGGAUCACCGGGCGUGGGACUUGCCGGCCCCAGCUCUGACAGGGCCCUAAGCAACAGAGGAAAGAACUUCCCGACUAACAGGGACAGCAACAUCAAAAGCGAUGGCUUUUGUGAAACUAAUUCAGCCACCUUGGAGCAGAGGAUUCCUCUGCUGGUUUCUGUUUCUGCCAGCUCUGUGCAGUGCAGGCGCUAUGAUGCUCUCUCUCUCUCACACACACAUACAGGGACCCGGGUGCCUCUCAGGUUGAGAGGGGUGGUCACCAUCCCCACACUCAGGCCCCCUCUGUCUCCAGGCCUGCUGCUUCUGAACAGGCCUGGGGCAGUCCAUUUCUAUUGGGAAACCCUAUCAAAGUUAGCCCCGGGUUUCAGCCAAGUUCACCUCACUGCUCACAGACAUUCAUUAUUAACAGACUGUUUGAUAGCACUUUGGGCUCUUUUUAAAUAAGACAUAGGAAGAAAGAUGCCAACGUCUCACUUGAAAUGCUCCUGACAGCUAGCCUGACGGGGUCCUGUCGCCCCUGUCCACACCCUGCUAUGGCCAUGGUCUCCACAGCCGCACAUGGGCUCCAGACAUUUUCACGAGUUAUGAACCAAAGAGAACCAAGACCCCUGGAGCAGGUUCUCCUUCUCAGUCCCAUGUUCCUUUGAAAGCAAUGAAUAGAGGCCAGGGAAGCAAGUGUUUAUACUCCAGUUUAGUACUAGUGAAACAUCGGGAAAUUCAUUGUGUUGGUAUCAAAGCCCCAACUCAGAACAUAAAAACCAUAAAACUGCAAAGCCUCUGCAGUCUGAGCGUGCGCUCCCCAGGCCUCCGCUGUCUGAGCGUGCGCUCCCCAGGCCUCCGCGGUCUGACCCUGUGCUACCCAUGCAAGCGCCACCCACAGGUGCGUCCUGGGGGCUGCCUCCUCCUCCACGUUGGCCAGCAGUGUGGGGUGUGACGGGGCCCAUGUUGUUGUCACCCCCACCCUGCCCCACGUUUCCCCUGCACACGUGUCCGUUCACAAAGAUUCUGAGCAAAAGGUCACAGAACAGCUUCCUCUGCCCUUUAUAUGUGGGGAGGAGGCCAAAGAUCUGCAGGCGUCAUCAUUCCAGGCCAGGGCUGGUAACAGGGAGCAAGUGCCGGCACCCUCUUGUGCUUCACAUGGGUUGGUUUACUUAACCCUCCUGUCUCAUGAAGAUUUUUACUAAGCCUGGGGAAACCGAGGCACACAGCAAGGAUGUCACCUGCCUGCAAAGGCACCUGUGUGCAAGCCAGGACUGGAAAAGCUCAGCCUGCAGUGCACAUGCUUGCUGCCCGCUCCAGAGCCCAGGCCCUUAACCACUUCCUUCCUAGGAAGACGGAGGGCGAGGGAGUUUCUUACAGCGCUUUAUGUCAACUCCUGCUGCUGCCCACCACUAAUCCAGGCCCCUGCAGACAGCAGGGCACGGUCCUUCCUAUUAGCAGGCUUACUACGAAGCCCUGUCUAACAUUCCCUCAUGUCAGGUAGAAGGAAUUAGACCAGAGGUCAAGGCAGCGGCUGGAAUCAGUGGUGCUUUCUCAAAGUAGGAAAACAGUUUUAGGACUGUUUUCGGUCAAAUUUUGGGCACCACUGUACUGGGUUCUAUGACAGAGAAGCCACCAAGGUCCCGUGCGAGGAGCCCUGGGCAGGGACAGCUGAAGCUGUGCACCUGGGCCCUCCUGAUUGCCUCCCACCAGCCAGGCCUGGCAGCAGCCAGCAGCCACCCCACCCCACCCCAACAAGGAGAGCUGCCCCACACUGUCGGCCCCCAAAGCUCAGGACACACGGGCCCUCCCAGGUCUCUCUGGCGGGCUAGGCCUUGGCAGGGCCCCCUCAGCGGGCCCCACUCUGAACCGCAAGCACAGGGUCUUCUGCAGUGUGAGACCUGCUGUCAGCACAGGCCUACGGGCUCAGGGCUGUGCAGGGACACAGGGGCCAGCACCACUGGGCACCCUGUCCUUUCCCAGCCUGCCUGUGCACCCUGUGGGCAGUGACUCCUCAGGCACAGUGGCCCAAAGUCACAGGUGGUCUGUCAGGGGCUCUCCAGGGAGCUGCACACACUCAGGUUUAGAUCAGGAACAGAACAGAUCCCCAGGGCAUUUGCUCAGGCUCAGAGCAGAGCAGGGAGCCGUCCACCUGCGGCGGGCACAUCCAUGGACUUCCAAGCCAACAGGGACAGCUGCCCAGACGGGCUGCCCAAGCCAACCAAGGAUCCUGUCCCAUCGGUCCCUGUGGCUUGGGAGUCUGGCACUUUUUGGCUUUCGUUUCUCAAGCUGCCCCAGCUUCUCCAAGUCCUGAGCCUGGGGCUCCCAGCUCCGAGCGGAUGCUCUGCAAGUGGCGUCCCUGCACCCUGGUGCAGGCGGACGGACGCGGGAGAGCCUGCAAGGAAGUAAGGCCCAGCAGCCUUCCCGGGCUUGGAACGCCGCAGCCUAGGAAGCAUCUUCCCAGGAAAUCGCAGUCGGAGCCCAGCACGGGGUCUUGGAAGAAAAGACCCCACCUUCUAUCCUCACGAGUACGCAUUAGGAGUGAGCACCGCUCAGUAGAUGACACAGAGGCACAGCUGAGGACCCAGAGACGGGCACACCGGAAACAGCGACAUCCACAGGCGCUCGGCAGGGACCAGGAACCCAGAAGGCUUGACGCGCAGGGGGUCUCGGAGAAACUCUACCCCUGUCCUUCCCAGCCUCCUGCUUAGCUGGGCCUCACCCUAGCCUGCUGGAGAUGGCGGCCAUGCCGUCAGAGAGGGGGAUGGACAGAUUGGCUGAGGUCACCCCACAGGCCAGCAGAGGCCUGGGUGGGAGUGCGCAGCCCCGCAGAUGGCUGCUUAUGGGGCCCAGAGGCCACCCCUGCGUCGCAGAGGGCACCAGCACACCCGGACUUCUCGGAGGCUUCAUACAGCUCCCAGGCCCUACAAGCAGCGUGUGGGCAGAGGCCCAGGCCCCUUCCUGUCACUCAGAGAAGCUGCUGCUCCCAGAAAACGGGGCGCCAGCCUCCCAUGAACACUGUGUCCCAACCCCGGUCCUCUCAGGAUUCCUGUGUGGAAAUGUCACUUCUGUCUCAGCUCUCUAGGGUGCACCUGGUGUCCAGCUCUGCCCCCUUUCUGCUUAAGCAGCUGCUGGGAGACCCUGAGCCAGGCCGCCGAGGUUCUGAGCUCGUAAGGGGUGCAGCAGUUUCCCGCACAGCGUGGGGAGCACAUUUGCUCACGUCUCCCAGGCUGGCUGUACACUCUGAGGCCAGCCCUGGGCUCUGACACUCUCCCGAUUCCGCUGGGCUUUCUAAGCCCUCCUCUCCUGUCCACUGCUGGCCCAUGGCCCAGGCCCAGCCUUGAAGCUGUAAAGACCUCUCACCCCAUCCAAAUGAGACUGGUCAGAUAUCUCCCGCAUGUCAGCCGCCACUGGAUUGGGAAGGACGGGCAGUAGGUGCAAGGCUGGCCCUUUUUAUGAGAGUUAUUUAAAAAACAAAAACAGGUCAGGCACAGUGGCUCACACCUGUAAUCCCAGCACUUUGGGAGACUGAGGCAGGAGGGUCACUUGAACCCAGGAGUUUGAGACUAGCCUGGGCAACAUAGUGAGACCCUGUCUCAAAAAACGUUAAAUGAAAACAUUAGCCAGCUGUAGUGGCACAUGCCUGUAGUCCCAGCUUCUUGGGAGGCUGAGAUGGGAGGAUCGCUUGAGCCCAGGAGGCAGAGGGUGCAGUUAGCUAUGAUGGUACCACUGCCCUCCAGCCUGGGUGACUGAGAGAGAUCCUGGCUCCAAACAGAAAAAUAAAAACAGAAGGAGGAACAGAUGAAUCCCAUUUGUGACAUUAAUGAAUUCUCUUAUAGGGAAAAUAAAACGAUUGAAACUGGGCCAUCUUGGACAGCUGAGGCCCAGGCAGGGCCAGCUCCUUCCACCUUCCCAGCCAAGAUGCUGCCUGCAGCCCCUCCCCUCCUGGCCCGAGAUGCUGUCAUUGUCCCUAAGAGACCCUGAGGCCUGCUCCAGGCUGAGUGGGUGAGGAGCCUCUGAGCAGGCGCCUGCGUCGAGGCGUGCCCUCCUGAGAGGCAAGGCUGACCUGCAGCGUCCAGCUCGGCUGGGGACACUCGCCUGAGAAGAGCCCAGUCCUGGGUGCCUCCCUAGGGGAGGGCCUUGGGGCUGCUUGUGCUGGCACCGACGUGGGCCUGGGGAGGGACCUGUGUGUGGGUGGCAGGUCUUGAGGAGUCGUGGGGGAGGGUUUCGGGGGGAGAUGCUGGUGGUAACAGUGGGAGGUAGGCAGUGAAACCAGCAGUGUGACUUUGGAGGUGCUGGAGGAGCAGGGCCUGGCGGAAGAAGUGGGGGAGCCAGGAAGGAGCAGCUGCCAGGGACGGCCUGGCCUGGGAGGGUGGCCAGGAACUGGGGGAGAAGCUGGUGGUCAAGCUGGUGGUCUCUCAGUGCAAGGGUGGGGCUGGCCUGGAGGAGAGGCCCACAGGGUCCCUGCUGGCUGAGGGUGCAGUGGCGGGCCCCGGAAGCUGAAUAUCACCCCCGCCACCGGGCAGGCAGUGCUCAGAGUGAAACGGGUGACUGGAGGGCAUGUGCCAGCUCUGUUCCUCAAGCCUGGCCCAAGAGGGACCUGCAGCAUGGGGUUGGGGGGCAGGCGGCCCUUCUCUGUGGUCUCUCCUGCCUUCUGAGGGAGCCUCCAGAAUCUUUCAUCGCCGCCACAACAAACUCAGGCUUUCGUGUAGGAAAAGAGCCCACUUCUGAAGAGGCUCAUCUGGGCUUUCUCUCCCAGCCUCUAAGUCUCCCAUCACCUGGCUCCCCGUUCCUCUUUCCCUUGAAGGAAGUCAGCAGAGUGCAUGGCUGACGGGAAAGAAGGCACAGCGGGCCUGCCCAGUGGGGGGAGAAGCCAGGCCAUUGUUCUCCAGUUCCAGGAUGCCCUGCUUCCCCAGACAGCCCGGCAGCCAGGAAAAGGAAGUCUCUGGGCACAGAGGCAAGCGGGAGACCACGGACAGGCAAGGAGUCGAAGGCUCCACCCGCCUGGGCCAGGCCAGGCUCCCACAGAACCCCUCUGCGUCCAGGCAGGCACAUGGGGCCCAGGCCAUCCCCCUCACUCGGACGCAGGUGUGGCGACGGCGGGGGAGGGGCGUCCACAGUAGAGCCCAGAACCUUGCGCAGGACAGGACCCCGGCUAAUGUGCCCGGAACAGCUCAGUGACAGGGAGCUGGGUUGGCUGUGAGGGUCGGGCACGCGUCACGAGUCUCCUGUGACCAGGAGAGGUGGGAACACUGGCUCACAUGACUCGCCAGGCCCUGGCACGCUGUGGUUCUGUGGGUGCCCCCUGCAGCUCCCAGCCUUCAAAAUGUACACCUCGCUGGGCAUGGUGGCUCACGUCUGUAAUCCCAGCACUUUGGGAGGCCGAGGUGGGCGGAUCACCUGAGGUCGGGAGUUCGAGAUCAGCCUGGCCAACAUGGAGAAACCUUGUCUCUACUGAAAAUACAAAAUUAGCUGGGUGUGGUGGCAGUCGCCUGUAAUCCCAGCUAUUCGGGAGGCUGAGGCAGGAGAAUCGCUUGAACCCGGGAGGCGGAGGUUGCAGUGAGCUGAGAUCGUGCCACUGCACUCCAGCCUGGGCAACAGAGCGAGACUCCAUCUCAAAAAAACAAAAACAAAACCAAAAAACCAUACACUUCAUGCUCACUUCUCUGGGAGCCAUGGCUAACAGCCUGCAGGCAGGAGACUCUCAAACCAGCUCCUGGAGGGCACUCCCAGGGACCCUGUUCCUACCACGAGCCAGAGAGGAGGCGGGUCAAGGAGACUUGUCCACCCAGGCGUGGCCGAGGAAGGGGUUUCCUCACGCUCUGCUGACCUGCCUUCCUUCCAUGCCUCUCAGCCCAGCUCCUGACAAAGGCGGGAACCUGAGCUCCUCGGCUUUAGGAACGUCCCCCAGAGCCCACGGAGCAGCCCGCCCCAGCUGCCUUCCCUCCCAAGAUCUCCAGGUAAUGCCUGGUAAAAGGAGGGCUCCAGGGAGAAUGUUGGGGCCAACACGCAAAGCGCGUCACCUUCCAACCGGCGGAGAGUGAAGGAAAACAGGUACGGCUCGGCUUGUAACCUUCACUGGAAACAGAAACCAUCCUCAUCAUUGAUACCUGGUGAACUGCACAGAGAGCAACCUGCAGCUUUGGAAGUUUAUAAAUCCUUCAGUAUUUGUCAGCUGCCAGUAAACAAAAAUGCACACAGGAGAACUUUCCACCUGAACCCCACCUGGAGGCCGGCGUUCCCAGGUCCCGGCUGGGGUGACAGCACGCACUCGAGAGCCGGUUCAGGGCGAGUGGGACGCACGUGAGCGCAGGGAGGAAAUGCCAGCAGAUCCCACUCCACGUGACCGCCUCCCAAGAAUCGAGCCAUUCUUAGCCCUGCAGACGCUGGCUGCCUCCCUCUGACUUGGCCUCACGGCGGGGCAGGCAUUAGCAGUCCAGGCAGCUUCUCUCUGACUCCCUGCAAGGAGGGGUGCGGCGGGCAAGAGGCUGGCCCCACGCGGUUCCACCUGCAGGAGAGCCCUCGCAGGAGGCUCCGUGUGUGGGGCCGGCUCAGCUUUUCUCUGGCCAUGCCCAUGUCCCUUCUGUGCACGGAGACACCAGAUGCACGUGCUCCCCUCUCUGCUUCCGACCUGAACCUGCCCUCGGCCUCCGCUGUGCCUCUGAGGACUCCUGUGUCCUGUGGGCUGAGUGAGCAUGGCCAGGCCUUCGCUCGACAGUAGACCCUUCUGUUGAUUUCCUCACGGAAAAAAGGGUUCGUAACCAACAUCUCAAGCACACUGAACACCAGGGGCGGCUGCAUGGACCUGGACACGUGUCUGCCUGACCUGCCCCCAGGCUCUCGGUGGGAUGCCCCGCAGCGAUGCAGACAGGGGCCUGCGGGCAGAGGCCACGGCCUCCAUGAGCCAGGCUAUCAGAAAGGUGGGACAAGAGGCCAGCUGUGCUCAGUUUGCAGUGCGGUCCCGUCCAAGCACGGCCCCUCGUUUCUGGAACCCGGCUGUAAACAGCAGGAGGGAGGGGCGGUGGCGCCUGCCAAGGGAGGCAGAGGCCCUGCGGGGAACUUACCAGAGGAAAACAAGUGCUUGCAUCCUGGGGCCCUCACACGCACGCGCAGGCGGCCAGGCGCGCUGCUGAUAAGAGCCUGCGGGUUUGCAGAGAAGCGCAGCAGCGCGCAGGUCCUCACCAGAGCUCUGGUGGCCACCUCUGUCCCGCCAUGCUGCUCACCGACAGUGGCCAGGGCCCACAGCACCAAGAGGCUUGGGCCACAAAGUAAAGGGUCGCGGAGCCUCGCCGGCCGCCAUGUGGAGCUGCAGCUGGUUCAACGGCACAGGGCUGGUGGAGGAGCUGCCUGCCUGCCAGGACCUGCAGCUGGGGCUGUCACUGUUGUCGCUGCUGGGCCUGGUGGUGGGCGUGCCAGUGGGCCUGUGCUACAACGCCCUGCUGGUGCUGGCCAACCUACACAGCAAGGCCAGCAUGACCAUGCCGGACGUGUACUUUGUCAACAUGGCAGUGGCAGGCCUGGUGCUCAGCGCCCUGGCCCCUGUGCACCUGCUCGGCCCCCCGAGCUCCCGGUGGGCGCUGUGGAGUGUGGGCGGCGAAGUCCACGUGGCACUGCAGAUCCCCUUCAAUGUGUCCUCACUGGUGGCCAUGUACUCCACCGCCCUGCUGAGCCUCGACCACUACAUCGAGCGUGCACUGCCGCGGACCUACAUGGCCAGCGUGUACAACACGCGGCACGUGUGCGGCUUCGUGUGGGGUGGCGCGCUGCUGACCAGCUUCUCCUCGCUGCUCUUCUACAUCUGCAGCCAUGUGUCCACCCGCGCGCUAGAGUGCGCCAAGAUGCAGAACGCAGAAGCUGCCGACGCCACGCUGGUGUUCAUCGGCUACGUGGUGCCAGCACUGGCCACCCUCUACGCGCUGGUGCUACUCUCCCGCGUCCGCAGGGAGGACACGCCCCUGGACCGGGACACGGGCCGGCUGGAGCCCUCGGCACACAGGCUGCUGGUGGCCACCGUGUGCACGCAGUUUGGGCUCUGGACGCCACACUAUCUGAUCCUGCUGGGGCACACGGUCAUCAUCUCGCGAGGGAAGCCCGUGGACGCACACUACCUGGGGCUACUGCACUUUGUGAAGGAUUUCUCCAAACUCCUGGCCUUCUCCAGCAGCUUUGUGACACCACUUCUCUACCGCUACAUGAACCAGAGCUUCCCCAGCAAGCUCCAACGGCUGAUGAAAAAGCUGCCCUGCGGGGACCGGCACUGCUCCCCGGACCACAUGGGGGUGCAGCAGGUGCUGGCGUAGGCGGCCCAGCCCUCCUGGGGAGACGUGACUCUGGUGGACGCAGAGCACUUAGUUACCCUGGACGCUCCCCACAUCCUUCCAGAAGGAGACGAGCUGCUGGAAGAGAAGCAGGAGGGGUGUUUUUCUUGAAGUUUCCUUUUUCCCACAAAUGCCACUCUUGGGCCAAGGCUGUGGUCCCCGUGGCUGGCAUCUGGCUUGAGUCUCCCCGAGGCCUGUGCGUCUCCCAAACACGCAGCUCAAGGUCCACAUCCGCAAAAGCCUCCUCGCCUUCAGCCUCCUCAGCAUUCAGUUUGUCAAUGAAGUGAUGAAAGCUUAGAGCCAGUAUUUAUACUUUGUGGUUAAAAUACUUGAUUCCCCCUUGUUUGUUUUACAAAAACAGAUGUUUCCUAGAAAAAUGACAAAUAGUAAAAUGAACAAAACCCUACGAAAGAAUGGCAACAGCCAGGGUGGCCGGGCCCUGCCAGUGGGCGGCGUGUGCUAGCAAGGCCUGCCGGGUGUGCCGCAGUCACCACAGGGUUCUGAGAACAUUUCACAGAAGUGCCUGAGACGCGGAGACAUGGCUGGUGUUAAAUGGAGCUAUUCAAUAGCAGUGACGCGCUCUCCUCAGCCACCAAAUGUCCCUGACACCCUCCCCAGCCCCCACAGAUAACAUCAGCUGAGGUUUUUUUCAGUAUGAACCUGUCCUAAAUCAAUUCCUCAAAGUGUGCACAAAACUAAAGAAUAUAAAUAAACAAAAGAAAGGUG